AAGUGUGAUGCCACCGCCGCUACGGGGAAGUAAUGGUAUCCGGCCAAUUGAGAUUCGGAGUUAAAACAGGGAUGUGCAGAUGGAGGUCGGAGGAGACACUGCUGCCCCGGCCCCCGGGGGCGCGGAGGACUUGGAGGACACGCAGUUCCCCAGUGAGGAAGCUAGAGAAGGUGGAGGGGUUCACGCGGUCCCGCCGGAUCCCGAAGACGAGGGCCUGGAGGAAACAGGAUCCAAGGACAAGGACCAGCCACCCAGCCCAUCACCACCGCCCCAGUCAGAGGCCCUGUCAAGCACCUCUCGGCUCUGGAGUCCUGCAGCCCCUGAGAAUAGUCCCACAUGUAGCCCUGAGAGUAGCUCUGGAGGCCAGGGCGGGGACCCCAGUGAUGAGGAGUGGCGCAGCCAGCGGAAGCAUGUGUUUGUGCUGAGUGAGGCUGGCAAGCCCAUCUACUCGCGGUAUGGUAGUGUGGAGGCGCUGUCGGCUACCAUGGGUGUAAUGACCGCCCUGGUGUCCUUUGUGCAGAGUGCGGGAGAUGCCAUCCGUGCCAUCUACGCUGAGGACCACAAGCUGGUGUUCCUACAACAGGGCCCACUGUUGCUCGUGGCCAUGUCACGGACUUCUCAGUCAGCAGCCCAGCUGCGGGGGGAGCUGCUAGCUGUGCACGCACAGAUCGUGAGCACACUUACACGUGCAAGUGUCGCCCGCAUCUUCGCACACAAGCAGAACUAUGACCUCCGCCGCCUGCUGGCUGGUUCAGAGCGCACACUGGACCGACUUCUGGACAGUAUGGAGCAGGACCCAGGAGCCCUGCUCCUGGGUGCCGUGCGCUGUGUGCCCCUUGCCCGCCCGCUGCGAGACGCACUAGGUGCGCUCCUCCGACGUUGCACAGCGCCUGGCCUGGCGCUGUCAGUGCUGGCAGUAGGCGGUCGACUUAUAACAGCAGCCCAGGAGCGAAAUGUGCUGGCCGAGUGCCGGCUGGACCCAGCUGACCUGCAGUUGCUGCUCGACUGGGUGGGUGCACCAGCCUUUGCGGCGGGUGAGGCUUGGGCACCUGUGUGCCUGCCCCGCUUCAACCCUGAUGGUUUUUUCUACGCCUACGUGGCCCGCCUGGAUGCUAUGCCUGUCUGCCUGCUGCUGCUUGGCACCCAACGUGAAGCCUUCCAUGCCAUGGCCGCCUGCCGGCGCCUGGUUGAAGAUGGGAUGCAUGCCCUUGGUGCCAUGCGUGCCCUUGGGGAGGCUGCCAGCUUCUCUAAUGCCUCAUCAGCCAGUGCUCCUGCCUACAGCGUGCAGGCUGUCGGGGCGCCGGGCCUCCGGCACUUCCUGUAUAAGCCGCUGGACAUCCCUGACCACCACCGCCAACUGCCCCAGUUUACCAGCCCUGAGCUAGAGGCCCCCUACAGCAGAGAGGAGGAGCGGCAGCGGCUGUCGGACCUGUACCACCGCCUGCAUGCUCGUCUCCACAGCACCUCCCGACCCCUGCGCCUCAUUUACCACGUGGCUGAGAAGGAGACACUACUGGCCUGGGUGACCUCCAAAUUCGAGCUCUAUACCUGCCUCAGCCCUCUGGUGACCAAGGCAGGUGCAAUCUUGGUAGUGACCAAACUCCUGCGCUGGGUGAAGAAAGAGGAGGACCGGCUCUUCAUUCGUUACCCACCCAAGUACUCCACACCACCAGCCACCUCUACGGACCAAGCUGCCCAUAAUGGCUUGUUCACUGGACUCUGAUAGUUGGAGCUCCCAGACCAGGCAGUGCUGGGAGCAACCACCUUUGUUUUUUACCUUCUGUCUACCCUGGAAAUGUGUGUGGGGGUGUGUCUGUGGCCAGUCAUUGUCUCCCUAAGCAAUGGGGCAAGGUCUGAGGGCCCACCGAUGAGAGAGAUGGUGGCAGCCGCCAGGCGAGCAGGCUGCUUUCCCUGCCCAGUCAUGCACCUCCCCCUCUGGGGAAAUCCUUAGGCCUCCCUCUCCCUUCCCUCUGUCUCAUCUCCUCCACUUGGAUGAUGCUCUAGCCUCUGUCAGGGACUGUCCCCUCCAAACUUGCUUCCGUGGUCUGCCUCCUAGUUGAAUCUCAGCCCUGAGUGUCCAGAUCUGGCCAAGGUGUCUAGGGUGGCCCACGGGGGUGCUGGAAUUGGCACUUCAGGGCCAGGCUAUGCUUGGGACUGGCCUGAGGGUAUUUUAAAGAAAAAAACUACAUAAAAGGCCUAAAAGUAAGACCCACAAGGAUAUUCCUUUGCCCUUCUUGUACUUUUUUCAUCUUUACCCUGCCAGAAAUGACCCGCCCUCAAUGCUGGCUGCUGCUAACAUUAAUGAGAAGGUGGCCUUCAGUGUCCACCUGUGGAACCCAGGACACAGCACCUGACUGCACACAGUGGCUGAAAUCCAGCAUUUUUACAUAGGAGAUGCACUUAGCCUCUAAGCCUCGUUUUACUCAUCUGUGAAACAGAGAUAAGUAACCCUCUCUCAUGAACUCUUUGAUGAGGAUUUGUAAACGAAAACAGACUCGAACUAUUGUGUACCACCACAUAGCACAUGCACGUCUGUCCCAGACUUUGACAACCUGCACAAGACAAGCAGCCUAAAGCAGGAGAGACCUCCCUAGGGUUUUGUGUGUGUGCACACUACCCUCACUCCCCAACUGGCCAUUACCCUAGUUCUGCCCUUGUUUGUGGAGUUACAGCCUCAAGGUUGUAGCAUGUGUGCUGGCAAUCAGGGCCGCAGUGUGUUCUGCGCCUGCCCAGAGCUGACUCCUGAUUUAACCGCUGGCGUAACCGCGGGUUGCACGCAUGCGUGCUGAAAAGCCUUUCACCCUCACGUGGUUUCUUUUUUAACCAGUCAUCAAGCGAGGCUCGCGCGCAGGCCCCGCGUUGGAAAAUGGCGGGGAAGCUGAAACCUCUGAAUGUGGAGGCGCCAGAAGCUACUGAGGAGGCUGAAGGUAGUGAGGGCAAGUGGGCUGCACUCCUUUCUCUCCAACCAGGGCAGAAAGGAGGGAGGAUUCGUCCCAUUACAAUAAUGAAAUAAUGAUAUUCUAAUUUUUUUAAAUAAAAUGUUAAGCCUUUUGUUAUUGAAGAAAAACAAUUUUUUAACCGUUCAGCACAGUGGAGAUAAAUUAACAGGCAUAUUCUUAUCACCGAGAUUAACUUUUGUCAACUGUAGUGUAUACGUUGUUGAAAGUAAACAACAUGUAGUUCAGUACGAAAGUCUUCAAACAAAAGUGGGGCGGUGGGGAUGUUCUCAUAACAAUCACCGUGCUGCAGCCACCCCUUAUUAACAGUAAUUCCCAGUGUCGCCAUUUCACACCUAACACAUAUGACACUUUGAUGGACUCUUAAACCUCCUAAUCGAACAUGGCCUCCCCCACAGCCUCUUUUCUCCAGGGUAUUGACUUGAAUGACAGGCAAAGGAGGGUGGAGGGGUGUCGGCCUAGACACUAUUGGAAAUUGUAUUCCAUCCAAAAGAAAAAAAAAUCUCAGGCCGGGCACGGAGGCUCACGCCUGUAAUCCCAGCACUUUGGGAGGCCGAGGCGGGCGGAUCACGAGGUUAGGAGUUCGAGGCCAGCCUGACCAACAUGGUGAAACACCAUCUCUACUAAAAAACUAUAUAUACAUAUACAUAUGUGUGUAUGUGUAUUUAUAUGUAUGUAUGUAUGUGUGUGUAUAUAUAUAUAUAUGUAUAUGUGUAUAUAUAUAUAUAUGUGUAUAUAUAUAUAUAUAUACACACACUAAUCAGCCGGGCGCGGUGGUGUGGGCCUGUAAUCGCAGCUACUCAGGAAGCUGAGGCAGGAGAAUCACUUGAACCCGAGAGGCGGAGGUUGCAGUGAGCCGAGAUCAUGUCACUGCACUCCAGCCUGGGUGACAGAGUGAGACUCCGUCUCAAAAGAAAAAAAAUUCUCCCUUGGCCGGGCUUGGUGGCUUAUGCCUGUAAUCCCAGCACUUUGGAAGGCCGAGGCGGGUGGGUCACCUGAGGUCAGGAGUUUGAGACCAGCCUGGCCAGCAUGGCGAAACCUCGUCUCUACUAAAAAUACAAAAAUUGUCCGGGUGUGGUGGCGGGCGCCUGUAGUCCCAGCUACUGGGGAGGCUGAGGCAGGGGAAUUGCUUGAACCCGGGAGGCAGAGGUUAUCGUGAGCUGACAUUGCGCCACUGCACUCCAGCGCGGAAGACAGAGUGAGCAAAAAAAAAAAAAAAAAAAGAAAAAACAAAAAGAAAAAAAUCUCCCAAGGCAGUCAUGCAUUUGUAUGCCACUAGCAUUUUUUUGUUAUAGAAAUAUUCAAAGUGUACCAACGUAGAGAAAAUAGCUUUAAACAAAGCCCAUGUGUACCUAUCAGUAUGCUUUAACUGUUGUCACCUUUCUGCCCCACUUUUAUCUAUCUCGAACACCCCUUUCUGCACACUCUUUAAACCACUGUAUUAACAAACACAUUAGACUGCAUCCUGCCAGACCUACCCAUACAGACAUCAAAGUAAUGAUUAUUGCUUAUUGCCUGACCUAGGAUGUGAGCUCCAUGAGAACAGAGACUGUUUACCUCUCGCUCCCCUGCACCUAAAACAAUGCCUGCUUGGUGUAAAGUAAGUGCUCAGUAAUUUUUUAAUGUGUGACCAAUGAAAUAACUUCAAGAGCAGAGAGCUCUUUUAGAUUAGAGGCACAUACUAAGUGCCAGCAUUCAACAAAAGACAGACGGAAAUAAGACAGAUGCAAAUAGAUCUCAUUUAUUAACUGUGUAAUGCAGCUGCCACUGCAAUUAAAAAAAAAAUUUUAGUAUCAACCUUUCAAAUUCCUCAAAAUUAAAGUUAUGACUAACUUCACCAGCAAAGGAAAAAUUGAAGGAUGUAUCAAGUUGCCAUUUCUAGCCCAUCAAAUCGGCUUUAUAAAGGGAAGCAUAGUAUCUGGUAUUGACGACCUUGUAGAGAAACAGGCCUUUUCCUGCCUCAGGGAAGAGAGCUGACUCAAAGUAAAGGCUUUGCUAGAGGCAGUCGGCAGAGUAUUUUUAGCAUCUAAAAUGCUCUUCCACUUCGGCAGUGACCAUGCGAUGUAAUCAAAGGAGAAUACGUAAGUGUAUGGACCAGGAAUGGUCACUGGAGUGUUGAUGUAGGCACAACACAAGAAGUAGUCACAGAAAUUGCUAAGUCUAGGUUUAUGUGUGCAUGCUGUGGAGUGUCUCUGUGGUGGAUUUCUUUUUAAGAGGCAGAAAAAAAUUCUAAUUUAAAUGUAUUAAAUUAUAAGUUCUAAUUUAAAUGUAUUAAAAUUAAAUUAUAAGUUGAUAGGAUUAUUAUUGACACACAAGGAGCUCCAAAAGAGAUCGUAUUUUUAUUAGAGACAAGCCAGUUGGGAUUGAAACAAAAAUGGAGGGGGGUAUAGCCCUGUGUAUGUUGCACAGAAAAAGUAUCUGAAUGAUAAAGGCCUAAGUGAUAACUCUGGACAAGGAAUUUGGAUUUUGGGAGUAGUGCAGAGGUAGAGGCAUUUUUGUGAUUUAUUGUUCUAUUUUUUCUUCUAGAAAAAUGUAAGUAGUCAUAUAUAAUUUUAAAAUAUAAAGGAGAAGAGGCAAAAUGUUGAAUGGCACCUGAGGAUCCUAUAUUCAUAUUGGAUCAGUAUUAACAUCCAGGUUUUGAUUGUUGUACUAUGGUUACCUGGUAGAUUCCCUUUGUAUAUAGGAAAUAGACACUGGAAUAGUAAGGAGUAGUGGGUCAAGAUGUCUGCAACUUAUUGUUCAGAAUCACUCACAAAUGGGAAAUCUGAUAUAAGGACAAAAUGGGAGCACUGUGGCCUAUUUUUACAACUUUUGUGUACAUCUGCAAUUGUUUCAAAAUAAAAUGUUUAAAAGGGU